GCUGGAGUUUCGCCGCCGCAGUCUUCGCCACCAUGCCGCCCUACACCGUGGUCUAUUUCCCAGUUCGAGGCCGCUGCGCGGCCCUGCGCAUGCUGCUGGCAGAUCAGGGCCAGAGCUGGAAGGAGGAGGUGGUGACCGUGGAGACGUGGCAGGAGGGCUCACUCAAAGCCUCCUGCCUAUACGGGCAGCUCCCCAAGUUCCAGGACGGAGACCUCACCCUGUACCAGUCCAAUACCAUCCUGCGUCACCUGGGCCGCACCCUUGGGCUCUAUGGGAAGGACCAGCAGGAGGCAGCCCUGGUGGACAUGGUGAAUGACGGCGUGGAGGACCUCCGCUGCAAAUACAUCUCCCUCAUCUACACCAACUAUGAGGCGGGCAAGGAUGACUAUGUGAAGGCACUGCCCGGGCAACUGAAGCCUUUUGAGACCCUGCUGUCCCAGAACCAGGGAGGCAAGACCUUCAUUGUGGGAGACCAGAUCUCCUUCGCUGACUACAACCUGCUGGACUUGCUGCUGAUCCAUGAGGUCCUAGCCCCUGGCUGCCUGGAUGCGUUCCCCCUGCUCUCAGCAUAUGUGGGGCGCCUCAGUGCCCGGCCCAAGCUCAAGGCCUUCCUGGCCUCCCCUGAGUACGUGAACCUCCCCAUCAAUGGCAACGGGAAACAGUGAGGGUUGGGGGGACUCUGAGCGGGAGGCAGAGUUUGCCUUCCUUUCUCCAGGACCAAUAAAAUUUCUAAGAGAGCUA